GGUGGCGGCUGCGGCAGUAGGGACAGCAGGAGCAGUGGUGCUGUCAGCGCGGCCGUCGGAGACAUGGGAGACCCGGGGUCGGAAAUAAUAGAAUCUGUCCCUCCAGCUGGCCCUGAGGCAUCUGAGUCAACAACGGAUGAAAAUGAAGACGACAUUCAGUUUGUCAGUGAAGGACCAUCGAGACCUGUUCUUGAAUACAUCGAUCUGGUCUGUGGUGAUGAUGAAAACCCUAGCGCCUAUUAUAGUGAUAUUCUGUUUCCUAAAAUGCCAAAACGACAGGGUGAUUUUUUGCAUUUUUUAAAUGUGAAGAAGGUGAAAACAGACACAGAAAAUAAUGAAGUGAGCAAAAAUCACUGCAGAUUGUCUAAGGCAAAGGAACCACAUUUCGAGUAUAUUGAACAACCAAUCAUUGAAGAAAAGCCAUCACUUUCAUCAAAGAAAGAAAUAGAUAAUCUUGUGCUUCCAGAUUGUUGGAAUGAAAAACAAGCAUUUAUGUUUACAGAACAAUACAAAUGGCUUGAAAUAAAAGAAGUUUACACAUGAAUAUGAGCAAAUUUUUAAAUUUAAAAUGAAGGCAUACUGAAAAAGAAUCAAGUGGCGAUGCAGAACCUAGUACAACUGGAACAGUAAACAGACUCAAAGAAGGUAUGUUGCAGAUUUGACAAUGAAUGGCAAUUGCAGUUUGCUGUGGCAGAGCAAAACAAGCUGCUAUUUAAGAAACAAAGUAGGAAAAUUGAGACUUCAGCAGAUGCAAAAUGAAUUGGGUAAAUUAUAUUUCAUAUGCCAAAAAGAAUCAAUGAAAUUUAGUCACCUAAAAUCAGAAUUAACAAGAGUUUUUAAAAACAAUUUUAGAAGGAACUAAGGUUGUAAGUUUGGCCAGAUGUGAAAUAGCUGAGAUUCUUUUUUUUUUUCCCGAGACAGAGUCUUGUGGUGUCACCCAGGCUGGAGUGCAAUGGCGCAAUCUUGGCUCACUGCAACCUCCACUUCCUGGGUUCAAGUGAUUCUCCUGCCUCAGCCUCCCGAGUAGCUAGGAUUACAGGAGUGUGCCACGACGCCUGCCUAAUUUUUUUUUUUUGAGACAGAGUCUUGUGUCACCCAGGCUGGAGUACAGUGGUGCAAUCUCGGCUCACUGCAACUUCCACCUUCUGGGUUCAAGCAGUUCUCCUGCCUCAGCCUCCCAAGUAGCUGGGAUUACAGGUGUCUGCCACCAUGCCCAGCUAAUUUUUUUGUAUUUUUUAUAGAGACGGGGUUCCACCUUGUUGGCCAGGCUGGUCUCAAACUCCUGACCUCAGGUGAUGCGCCUGCCUCAGCCUCCCAAAGUACUAGGAUUACAGGAGUGAGCCACCAUGCUCAGCAAAAUAGCUGAGAUUCUUGCAUGAAAGAAUUAGGGUUUUUUUUUUUUUUGGAUGGGAGAGGGGAGGGUCCUGCUAUGUCACCCAAGCUGGACUGCAGUGGCUCACUGCAGCCUCUUCCUCCUGGGCCCAAGCAGUCCUCCCACCUCAGCCCCCUAAGUAGCUGGGAAUACAGGUACAUGCCACCACACCCAGCUAGUUUUUAUAUCUUUUUGUAGAGAUGGGGUUUUGCCAUGUUGCCCAGGUUGGUAUUGGACUCCUGGGCUCAAACAGCCUUCCUGCCUUGGCCUCCCAAAGUGCUGGGAUUAUAGGCAUGAACCACCAUGCCUGGCUGAGAACUAGUUUUAAAUGGAUAAAUGUGAAAUUAUUUCAGUUGAAGAAAUUGUUAGAAAAUUAUGAAUAAAAGCCUAAAUAAGAUGUUUUAUUAAAAAUUACAAGGCCUUGCUGGGUGCUGUGGCUCAUGCCUGUAAUCCCAGCACUUUGGGAGGCCGAGGCAGGUGGAUCAUGAGGUUAGGAGAUCGAAACCAUCCUAGCUAAUAUGGUGAAACCCCAUCUCUACUAAAAAUACAAAAAAUUAGCUGGGCCUGGUGGCAUGCACCUGUAGUCCCAGCUACUCGGGAGGCUAGGGCAGGAGAAUCGCUUGAACACAGGAGGCGGAGGUUGCAGUGAGCAGAGAUCACACCACUGAACUCCAGCCUGGGCGACAGAGCGAGACUUUGUCUCAGAAAAAAAAAAAAAGUACAAGGCCUUUAGUUAAGCACCAAACAAUUGCUAUUAGAAUAUAGGACCUAGCAAUAUUAAAGAUUAAUUGAUUCUAAAUCUGAAAAAUCAUAAGUACAUUUCUGUAGUUUUAGAACAGUUUCAUAAUUUGAGAAACUACCCAAGUAACACACUACAUUGAGUCUCAUAGGACUUAAAAAUUAUGAAGAAAUAAUUUCAAUUGAUGGCCCCAAAAGUCAAAUUUAUGGCCAGGUGCAGUGGUUCACACGUGUAAUCCCAGCACUUUAUGGGAGGCCGAGGCAGGUGGAUCACCUGAGGUCAGGAGUUCGAGACCAGCCUGACCAACAAGGUGAAACCCCACCUCUACUAAAAAUACAAAAUUAUCCAGGCAUGGUGGCAGGUGCCUGUAGUCCCAGCUACUCAGGAGGCUGAGACAGGAGAAUUGCUUGAACCUGGGAGGCAGAGGUUUCUGAGCUAAAAUCGCACCACUGCACUCCUGCCUGAGCGACGGAGCAAGACUCCAAGUCAAAAAAAAACAAAAAACAAAUUUAUGCAGCUGUUUUUUUAAUAAUUAAAUGUUAAUUAUUAUUAUUUUUUGAGACAGGGUCUUGCUUUGUCGCCCAGGCAGUGGCAUGAUCAUGGCUUACUGCAACCUCUGUUUCUAGGCUCAAGCAAUCCUCCCACCUCAGCUUCCCAAGUAGUAGGGAUUACAGGCACAUGCCACCACAAUCGGCUAGUUUUUGUAUUUUUGGUAGAGACAGGGUUUCCCCAUGAUGCCCAGGCUGGCCUCGAACUCCCUGGUUCAAGUGAUCCACCCGCCUUAGCCUCCCAGAAUGCCGAUAUUACAGGUGUGAGCCACCGCGCCCAUCUCAUGCAGCUUUUAAAAUCUCUGCGUGUGUUAUAACAGUUUCAGCUAGAUGAGAAAAAAAAAACAUUUUCUGUCACAAUAAAUGGCACUCCAGCUAAGUUAGGUUAAAAAAAAUUAGAUUUCAUUAGAAUUUUAAAACAAACUUGAUGUUUCUGUUAUUUCUUCAUUCCACUAAAUGAUAUGGUUUGAAAAUAUUUAUGCUCAGAUUUUUAAAUGGUCUCUACAACAAAUUGUCACUUGUUGGGUUCAAUUAAGUGCUCAUUGUAUAAGUGCACAUGGUACAAAUCAACACCAGCUUAUAGGAUUGUGGAAAGAAUUAAGAGAUGAAUUUAGUGAUCUUAUAUACCCUGUCAGUUGGUCAUAUUGUGGAAGAGCUCUACAAAACUUACUGUACUGUUAACUCCAAGAUUUUCUUCCAAUAACAGGGAUGCUAGCCAGAUAUUUAAUAAUCAAAGACCAAAAAUGGCAGUUUAAUUUUUCUACCCAAUAUCCUAUGGCAUAUGAAUGAUCCAAAUUUGAAGCUCCAAGGAUAGGAAAAAGCUUACUUGUGCCUGUCCUAGACAAGUACUAGAGUUUAUAUUGAAAUCAAAACUUCUAAAAAUAAAAAUCAGUAAGAUUAAUUUUACUCAUUUUUCUAACACGAGUCAGUAUGCUUGAAGUUUUCAUUGUAUUUGAUGUCAUGUAAAUUUACUGUAAAAAAUAAGAAAAAAUUUUAAAAUGCUUUAUUGAUUAAAUUUAGGGUUGCUUUUCAGUAUACUCAGUAACUCCGAAGUCAGUGUUAACAGUACUGAGCUUACAUAAGAUUUAUUGAAUUUACCUAACUUAGGCAAAUGUUUUCAAACUUAUAUGCUUUUGGUCCAAAGUCAAAUCAAUUAUUUUGAAAAAGAUGAAUGGGAUUUUUUUCAGUGUGGAUAUGAAAAAUAAAAUAAAAUGAUAGCUAUGUUUGGAACAA